GUUUUAGCCGGUGGCUGCUGUCUCUGGGCGGGCCGUGGGAGGCUCCCGAGGUGGGGGCCGGGGCGGGAUGGCUGCAGCGGCGGCCGGGGCCGGGAGCGGGCCCUGGGCGGCCCAGGAGAAGCAGUUCCCGCCGGCGCUGCUGAGUUUCUUCAUCUACAACCCGCGCUUCGGGCCGCGCGAAGGACAGGAGGAAAAUAAGAUUUUAUUUUAUCAUCCAAAUGAGGUAGAAAAGAAUGAGAAGAUUAGAAAUGUCGGAUUGUGUGAAGCUAUUGUACAGUUUACAAGGACAUUUAGCCCAUCAAAACCUGCAAAAUCUUUACAUACACAGAAGAACAGACAGUUCUUCAAUGAACCAGAAGAAAAUUUCUGGAUGGUCAUGGUUGUUCGGAAUCCUAUAAUUGAAAAACAGAGUAAAGAUGGAAAACCAGUUAUUGAAUAUCAAGAGGAGGAGUUGUUGGACAAGGUUUAUAGCUCGGUGCUGCGGCAGUGCUACAGCAUGUACAAGCUUUUUAAUGGUACAUUUCUGAAAGCCAUGGAAGACGGAGGCGUCAAGCUUCUGAAAGAAAGAUUAGAGAAAUUCUUCCAUCGGUAUUUGCAAACGCUACAUUUGCAGUCAUGUGACCUACUUGACAUUUUUGGUGGAAUCAGCUUCUUCCCGUUGGAUAAAAUGACUUAUUUGAAAAUCCAGUCCUUUAUUAAUAGAAUGGAGGAAAGCCUGAAUAUAGUCAAAUACACUGCUUUUCUCUAUAACGAUCAGCUCAUCUGGAGUGGAUUAGAACAAGAUGACAUGAGAAUUUUAUACAAAUACCUUACCACCUCCCUUUUUCCAAGGCACAUCGAACCUGAGUUAGCAGGAAGGGAUUCUCCAAUAAGAGCAGAAAUGCCAGGAAAUCUUCAACACUAUGGAAGAUUUCUUACCGGACCCUUGAACCUCAAUGAUCCAGAUGCAAAAUGCAGAUUCCCCAAAAUUUUUGUAAAUACAGAUGACACUUAUGAAGAGCUCCAUUUAAUCGUUUAUAAGGCCAUGAGUGCGGCUGUGUGCUUUAUGAUCGACGCCUCUGUCCACCCAACGUUGGAUUUUUGCCGAAGACUGGACAGCAUCGUUGGGCCCCAGCUCACAGUGCUGGCCUCUGACAUCUGUGAACAGUUUAACAUCAACAAGAGGAUGUCCGGGUCUGAGAAAGAACCCCAGUUUAAGUUUAUCUACUUCAACCACAUGAAUCUCGCCGAGAAGAGCACAGUUCACAUGAGGAAAACGCCCAGCGUGUCGCUCACUUCCGUGCACCCGGAUUUAAUGAAGAUUCUCGGUGACAUCAACAGUGACUUUACCAGAGUGGAUGAAGAUGAGGAGAUCAUUGUGAAGGCCAUGAGUGAUUACUGGGUUGUUGGAAAGAAGUCUGAUCGGCGGGAGCUCUAUGUUAUUUUGAAUCAAAAAAAUGCAAACCUGAUUGAAGUAAAUGAAGAGGUCAAGAAACUUUGUGCAACGCAGUUCAACAACAUCUUCUUCUUGGAUUGACGGAUGACGGCUCACCGAGAGCAUAUCUAAAAAACACUCUGCAAACAUUUGGUCACAUGCAAGUUAGUGGUCAUAUGACGGACUGCAUUCAGGACAAGGGUAAAGCAAUACUUGCUUUGAAGAAUCACAUUUCGACUCGGUCUGCUGAUCUGAGGUUUUUAGAUUUUAAAUAUUUAUGUGGAAUUAAUUAAAGGUAGUUGGCUAUAUCGCUAUCAUUUCAUUCUUUUGACAUUAUGUGAAUAUUUUACUGGAAAAUAAGACUAAUAAAUUGUUAAAAGUUUUUAAAAUUCUGGUUUGGUGUUGAGUCUCUCUCCUGCUGCCUAUUUAUAGAUUACACUGGCCACCAGCUCCGUGACCCAGGCUGGAAUGCAAUGGCUCACUGCAGCCUCAACCUCCUGAGCUCAAGCAAUCCUCCCACCUCAGCCUCCCAAGAAGCUAGAACCACAUGUACACACCACCACGGUCGGCUGAUGUUUUAAUUUUGCAGAGAUGGGGGGGUCUCACUAUGUUGCCCAGGCUGGUCUCGAACUCCCGUAAUCCAGCCAUGUAGGAAACCUGAGAUGCAGUGGGCCAAGGGGUAUGUUAAAACACUGUGACGAGUUCAGUGCUAAGAACUGUAAUGCUCAGGAAAUCUUACAGCACGUGCCAUCCUAAGCCUGUGUGUGUGUCCUCGUGUCUCUCUACUUUUUCUUCUUCUUGCUGGUGAUGGUCUUGCUGGAUGGGGACACGGUCACAUCCUCCUUGGGAGGGUCCAGUAUGAGGUGAGAGGAUGACACGUCUGCCGGCUCCUUGAGCACUGUGAUGUCCACCUCAUAGUCAUGUCUCUUGGCCUCUUCCUCUCUCAAGAUGAAGAUGUUCAGCCU